ACGCGGAACCUCGGCGCGGUGCUUCCAGCAGGGUCUCUCCGCCACUCCAGCCCCGCGCCCCUCGCCGCGGCCCUCGGGCGUCUGCGCCGCAGCUGCCGCCCCCGCCUCUUUGGAGUCUCUCGCGGCCUCAAAGCGCGGCCUGCGUCGCUUCCGGCAGUUCCCGACCGCGGGCGAUGGCUGCCGCUGGGGGCGCCCGGCUGCUGCGCGCCGCUUCUGCUGUCCUCGGCGGCCCGGCCGGCCGGUGGCUGCACCACGCUGGGUCCCGCGCUGGAUCCAGCGGCCUGCUGAGGAACCGGGGGCCGGGCGGGAGCGCGGAGGCGAGCCGGUCGCUGAGCGUGUCGGCGCGGGCCCGGAGCAGCUCAGAAGAUAAAAUAACAGUCCACUUUAUAAACCGUGAUGGUGAAACAUUAACAACCAAAGGAAAAGUUGGUGAUUCUCUGCUAGAUGUUGUGGUUGAAAAUAAUCUAGAUAUUGAUGGCUUUGGUGCAUGUGAGGGAACCCUGGCUUGUUCAACCUGUCACCUCAUCUUUGAAGAUCACAUAUAUGAGAAGUUAGAUGCAAUCACUGAUGAGGAGAAUGACAUGCUCGAUCUGGCAUAUGGACUAACAGACAGAUCACGGUUGGGCUGCCAAAUCUGUUUGACAAAAUCUAUGGACAAUAUGACUGUUCGAGUGCCUGAAACAGUGGCUGAUGCCAGACAAUCCAUUGAUGUGGGCAAGACCUCCUGAACUAGAACAAAUAGGAAUAUUUUCAUGGAAUUUUACCUAUUUUUAUAAUUAUUAUUUCUUAAAGUGAUUAAAUGAGAACAUGGAUGAGUGGACUUCAUAUUAUGACUAGCUUUACUAUUUUAAUUCACCUUGCAUAACUACUGAAUUUUGUCAUUCUUGAAAGUAUGCAAUUUUUAUUUUGGUUAUAUUACAAAAAUGUCAAUCAAAUAUUAAAAAAUAGUUAAUGUGAUAGAAAAACCUUACAUAUUUUUUUCUUAUGUUUGUUUAGCGACUUUAGCAAAAUGUUUUCAUAUAAUCUCAUCUGUUUACCUAGAAGAUAGGUUAAGGAAAUAUAUUAUUAUUCCUGUUUGAUGUGGGUGAAGGCAGAGAUCUAACCUGGCUUGUUUAGGGCCAUACCACUAAUUAGAAAAUCUGUGCUAGAACCUGUGUCUUAUUCCUAUAAGCUAUGUGUUCAGACUGAAACUGGAGAAAUUAUGACUAUUUUAUUUAUAGUAGUAGUUAAAUCUGAAUGUGUAUGGACAAAAAUAUUUAAUUGCUCAGUAAACUGCUUAACUUCAAAGAUAGUUAUUGACCUUAUAAAUAAAUAUUUCAAAAUUUUGAUUCGGAAGACUAAGUCUGGACGUAGACAUUAUAAUGCUAUCAAAGAAGUUUGAUCUCUGUUUUGACUAAACUAGAGGAAAAAUGAUUGGAUGUGUUUAUUCUUUUCUAAGCAGAAUGGUUUAACUUUGUACUCUUUGAAAAAUAAUGCUGAUUUAUAAAUCUCUGCCUAUAACAGAAUGGAAACCUUAUGAAUGAAUUGUGUUUCUCUGUCCUGAGCUGGAGAAGGGAAUGAGCAGGCUGACACGUUGCACAGCCCCAGGUGGCGCCAUUCUCUCACGCAAGGAUGGGGCUGCAGGGUGAGCAGCGUGGGCUGCAGUGUGUCAGUCCCAGGAGUGAGGGAGUGGCAAGCACCACAGAUUACCACGUAUGUGUGGAAGACAUUCGUACUCUUAUCUUUACUAUAAAUAAAUUCAUAAAAGUUAACAAAGGGGUACACAGUAUGGUCUUUGGAAAUAUAAUAAAACAUCAACUAACUUGGACUAAUUGUGAGGAAGAGCAGAACAAAUUAGUAGAAAGAGGUUAUAAGACAAUUGAGUUAGCUUCAUGUGUAUUAUUGCAGCUUGAUCAUUUAUAUAAAUAUUUGUCUAGUACAAUGCUUGACAUACAGCAUUGUGUUAUGCCCAUUGGGGACACAGAGGUGAACAAGACAAGGAAUGCCAUCAGGGAAUUCACCUUUUAUUAGGAAAAUAUAAAAUAUGUAUGUAUGUGCAGAUAAUUUGCUUGAACUAAACUGACUAGUUCUGCUAAAUAAGAUUUUAAACUAAUUCAUAUGUAAAAAGUGAUUAGGAAGAACUUGAAGUAUCAUUUGAUGCUUAAUAACUAUUGAGUAGUUUUUUUUUUUUUUUUUUGGUGGGGGGAGCGGGGGACAGGGUCUUACUCUGUCACUCAGGCCAGAGUACAAUAGUAUGAUCUCGGCUCACUGCAACUUCUGCCUCCCAGUUUCAAGGGAUUCUCGUGCCUCAGCCUCCCAGGUAGCUGGUACUACAGGCACGGACCACCACGCCUGGCUAAUUUUUGUAUUUUUUCUAGGGACAGGGUUUUACCACGUUGCCCAGGCUGGUCUUGAACUUUUGAGCUCGAGUGAUCCACCCACCUCAGCCUCCCAAAAUGCUGGGAUUACAGAUGUGAGCCACCGUGCUUGGCCAUAACUAUUGAAUGCUUUCUAUGUGGAGAGUGCUUGUCUUAAUUUUCUGUUGCUAUAAUAGAAUAACACAGACUGGGUAAUUUAUAAAGAAAAGAGAUUUAUUUGGAUCAUGGUUCUGGAGGCUGGGAGGUCCAAGAGCAUGGUACCAGCAUCUGCUUGGCAUCUGGUGACAGCUUUCUUGCUGCAUCAUUACAUGGUGGAAGGGCAAGAGAAUGCGAGUGAGAGCAAGAGGGCAAAAUGAUUAUCCUUUUAUCAGGAGCCCACUUCUGACAUAACUAACCCACACCUGAGAUAACGGCAUUAAUCCAUUCAUGAGGUCUCUGCUCUUAAAGGAGAUCACCUCUUAAAGGACCCACCUUUCAAUGCCAUUACACUGGCAAUUUAAUUUCAAGAUGAGUUUUGGAGGGGACAUUCAAACCAUAGCAGUGCUAUAAUUUUAAAGUACUUCAAAGCCAAUUUAUUCUCUUAAUUAGCUUCAUUAUUCUUGUCUUUGUGUGUGGAUUACCUAAACUCUCCUUCCAGAGCUACUUUAAUGAUUAUAUUCAACCAAAGCACUCUAAAAUUUAGAGUAUAAAUUGUCUUAUAUUUCAAAUUAGAAAAGUUCAAAUGAAGUUUAAUUGUGUUAUUUUAUAAAACCUUCUAAAAUUAUUAAAUGGAGGAUAUAAUCUAUAA